GCCUCCCCUCGCGCCGGGAGGAGCUGGCGGCGAGCGCCGAGCCGGGCGCGCAGCGACGGAGCUGGGGCCGGCCUGGGACCAUGGGCGGUGAGUGCGGCGCGGGCCUGGGCCGGGGCGGUUGCCGUUGGGGCCGAGCAGCGCAGAGGUUCUAGGCGGGUGGGCGUCCAGGGUCCGAGGUUGGGAGACUGAGGGGGUCCCCCUAACUCGCCAGUGGGAGAGGGGCGGGAAGGCUGGGGGCGCUUCGAAGCGUCGGGUCCGAAUCCCGCGACUAAGCCUCCUCCUUUAUCCCCGCGCUCGCCCCUGAGCCUAGGACUUGCGCCCUCUUUCCUGCCACUCCCCCCGUGCGCCCGGUGUCCCAGCCCCGGCGCCCGCCCCAUAGCCCCCUUCUCCCAGAGCUGGCGCCGUCUCACGCCCGCUGCGAACCCCCGGCUCUGUCUCCAAGCCCUCGCCCCCCGCAGCCCCGCACUCUCCCGCGGAGCCCGCCUCCACCUCGCCCCCGCCCUUCCAGCCCUCUCCCGCACGGCCCCCGCACUCCCGCCGCUGGAUUCCAGCCGAGAUUCAAGCUCCCGGGAUCCCCCUUCCCGGGCGGUCCUGAGCCGGCUAGUCUCCAGUGAGUGCAAUCUACGGAUCAGUCUCUGAUGGUGGGUCGUUAACCUCAGUGGGGACUCCAAGAUUUCCAUGAAGAAAAUCAGUUGUCUUCAUUCAAGAAUUGGGAUUGUCUCUGUCUUCAGGUCUGGCUCAGAAUUCCUGCAGCUGGUGAAAAUCUGUUUUCUAGAAGAGGUUUAAUUAAUGCCUGCAGUCUGUGAGCCCUGAGCUGUAGCCCCAGUCCCCUUUGACAUCACCCAUUUUCCAAUGGAGGAAGCUUCCAGGGAGACAGGGUACCACUUGGAGAGCCCCCAUGGCCACUUCAGAUUGCAGCCAUUGCCACUUCAUCUCACCUGAGGUGCUGAGGGGAGAGUCUAGGUAAGUGACAAAAGGAGCAGUGGCUUGGAAGGUCUGUGCACCUGUAUUUAGGAGGUGAAGAAGAGGGAGCAGCUUUCUAGUAGGAUGGUGGGCCUUUUGAUAGAAGCAUCUCCCAGGGACUCUUUUUGAACCUGCUGUGCAGCCUUGCAGGUAAACGACGGCCCAUUGGAGCCUCUCAACCUGGAGAUGCUGCAUGGCAGCCACGAGGAGGCACCCGUGAACCCAGAAUGAAUUUCAGGGUCCGCUCUGAGUCCAAAAGGCAGGAGGGCCCUGGCCAACUAACACCUAACUGAGCCACAGACUCUGGCCUGUUUAUCCUCCACCCUCAAAACCAGCAGGCUUCUCUGACCCUUUUUGGACUUUGGCUGGGGAAGCCACUGGCUUUUGGAAAAAGUUCAGUCUGCAGUGAUGGCGGGAACAAUCUCAGGAGUCUGGAAGAAGUUAAUGAUUAAAAAGGCAUGGAAGAAGAACUGGAUGGCGGCUUGGGGAGUAGUUUCUGCAGUCAGGAGGCACCCUUCACCUCAUUCCCUUGGCCCACAGUCAUCUGUGCAUGCGUCUGCCCCUCCCUCCAUCAGUGGAGCUCCCUCUGAGCUGCGUACUCGAGGGUGGAGGAGAGUUUGGGGGAACUCAAACAUGUGGUAGUAGAGACUGUAGUAACUUUAAAAUUCUCUUUGUAUUUGCAGAAUCAUUUCCCCAAUUUACACACUCAUGUUUCAGUUUACAGGGCAUCCUUUUGUCACCUGCUCGCCACCCUUAUGCCCCUGGGUGUGACCAGCUUCCUCAGAAAGAGCUGUAAUCAAUAGCAUAUUGAUUAAAAAGCAUAUUAAGAUGAAAAUUAUUGCACCUGGUUUUGAUGCCCCCACUCUCUCCCCUUUCCUCCUCCACUUCUGUUUGUGGUUACAGCCAUCAUUUACAUUAAAGUUACAAAUCAUUUUGAAUACUAUUUGUCCCACCCCUCAGUUAUUCAGAGACAUGUGUCUUUUCAACCAACAAAACCACAGCUUGCUUUCCUAAGCUUACCUCAUUCUUGGAUCUAACACCAACCUUCAGGCCUUCAGAGAUCCAGCAGUAUCAUUUUGAGCUUUUAACCGUAAAAUAAAAUGAAGCUCUUACUUGCUGUUUGUUCUCUGCAGACAUAGGAGAAUCUAGUUAGAAUUAAACAUUUACUGUCUUGUUAAGGCUUUAUGCUUCUAAAAUGAAAGUGGCAGUUGGAUUACCGUAAAGUUAGUAAAGUUGUAGAACAAAUUUUUGGAAGCUCAGAAAUAAUAAUGGAGGGACUUACAGAAAUAAACUAUUAAGCUUAAAUCUUAAAACAUAGAUAUAAAUAUGAACUAUCUUGAAAGUAUAGAAAAUUUGGCAAGUAUAGAUUAAUAAGUAUAUAAUAUUUUAUGCAAGUUAUAUUAAUUAUUAGGAUCAUGCAUUAUGUUUAUACAGUACCUUACUAUAUAAAAAAGCAACUUUGUCCAUAUCUCAUUUGAUUCAAUAAGCCUGCGAUCUGCUUAGAGAUGGGGAGAUGGGACCUUGGGAUGGUUAAAAGGCUUCCUCUAGAAUUCAGAUCUCAUAAGCAGAGAAAUACUAUGUAAACCUGGAUAUCCCUGCCCACGUUGCUUGAUAACCAAAUGUGGUUACAUAGUUUUUUGAAAAUUGUAGGUGGUCCUAUUCUUAGGGAUAAAAAUAGGCAUUGGUUUUCUCUAAAACUUUCUGCAAGUCAAACAAACAAACAAAAACUCUGUAUGUAGCACCCAGAAACCUGAAAGGACUUCUCAAGGUUUGUAGAUGUCAGAGGUUCUCUGUUGAUGACUUCCUAAUACUAGAGUACCUGAGUUGGUUGUGUAUUCAGCACAGUGCAGUGAUUGAGUGUGUACAUUCAGAGGCCAAACUGACUUUAAACCCUGGCUCUACCAUUACUAGCAAUGUACCCUUGAACAAGUUACUUCUCUGUGCCAGUUUCCUUAUUUGUAAAAUUUGGGUGGUGAUAAUAAUACCUACUUCAUGGUACUGUUGUGAAACUGAAAUAUAAUAAUACAUGAUGAGGGCUUAGAAAAGCACCUACCACAUGGUACAUGCUUUAAAAAUGUUAGCUGCUAUUCCUAUUCAUUUGUUUCUUAAAAUUACCUUUUAGGCGCCAACUGACUGCACUGAGAUGAUGGAUACAGGAUAAUAGUCUCUGUCCUCAUGGAACAGAGGACAUUAUAUUUCAGUUUGUGGUGAAGGACAUGAAUGGCGGUGCAGAUCGAUUUCCAGGCACUUGCUCACUUACAGCCAUGAGAGGCUGUGAAGGGGCUGACCAUGGGGUGGUGACCUUGCCAGCUCUUUGAAACAGGCACUCAUUUUGACUCAUCUGUGUCUGACACAUGCUGGUUGUUUUAACUGUCACUCUUGGCCACAGGUUGUUAGUGGGAAGCAUGAUAAGAGAUCCUAGAUCUGUUUAGUCACCUGGUUUUGCCAACACUAUUUUUGGUCCUGGUUGACAGAAUGCUGCCCUGGCUACUAUUUUGGACUGGACUGGCUCUUCAGCAGCCCCAGAAACCUUUGGUACUAUCAGAGACCCAGUUCUCUGAGCAAGAAAUGGCACAGCUGCUCCUGAGAGCAGGACAUGUUCCCGAUUUGAGGUGAAACCAUGAAGAGAAAAUAGAAUACUUAAUAAUGCUUUUCCGCAACCGCUUCUUGCUGCUGCUGGCCCUGGCUGCGCUGCUGGCCUUUGUGAGCCUCAGCCUGCAGUUCUUCCACCUGAUCCCGGUGUCGACUCCUAAGAAUGGAAUGAGUAGCAAGAGUCGAAAGAGAAUCAUGCCCGACCCUGUGACGGAGCCCCCUGUGACAGACCCCGUUUAUGAAGCUCUUUUGUACUGCAACAUCCCCAGCGUGGCCGAGCGCAGCAUGGAAGGUCAUGCCCCGCAUCAUUUUAAGCUGGUCUCAGUGCAUGUGUUCAUUCGCCACGGAGACAGGUACCCACUGUAUGUCAUUCCCAAAACAAAGCGACCAGAAAUUGACUGCACUCUGGUGGCUAACAGGAAACCGUAUCACCCAAAACUGGAAGCUUUCAUUAGUCACAUGUCAAAAGGAUCCGGAGCCUCUUUCGAAAGCCCCUUGAACUCCUUGCCUCUUUACCCAAAUCACCCAUUGUGUGAGAUGGGAGAGCUCACACAGACAGGAGUUGUGCAGCAUUUGCAGAACGGUCAGCUGCUGAGGGAUAUCUAUCUAAAGAAACACAAACUCCUGCCCAAUGAUUGGUCUGCAGACCAGCUCUAUUUAGAGACCACUGGGAAAAGCCGGACCCUACAAAGUGGGCUGGCCUUGCUUUAUGGCUUUCUCCCAGAUUUUGACUGGAAGAAGAUUUAUUUCAGGCACCAGCCAAGUGCGCUGUUCUGCUCUGGAAGCUGCUAUUGCCCGGUAAGAAACCAGUAUCUGGAAAAGGAGCAGCGUCGUCAGUACCUCCUACGUUUGAAAAACAGCCAGCUGGAGAAGACCUACGGGGAGAUGGCCAAGAUCGUGGAUGUCCCCACCAAGCAGCUUAGAGCUGCCAACCCCAUAGACUCCAUGCUCUGCCACUUCUGCCACAAUGUCAGCUUUCCCUGUACCAGAAAUGGCUGUGUUGACAUGGAGCACUUCAAGGUAAUUAAGACCCAUCAGAUCGAGGAUGAAAGGGAAAGACGGGAGAAGAAAUUGUACUUCGGGUAUUCUCUCCUGGGUGCCCACCCCAUCCUGAACCAAACCAUCGGCCGGAUGCAGCGUGCCACCGAGGGCAGGAAAGAAGAGCUCUUUGCCCUCUACUCUGCUCAUGAUGUCACUCUGUCACCAGUUCUCAGUGCCUUGGGCCUUUCAGAAGCCAGGUUCCCAAGGUUUGCAGCCAGGUUGAUCUUUGAGCUUUGGCAAGACAGAGAAAAGCCCAGUGAACAUUCCGUCCGGAUUCUUUACAAUGGCGUCGAUGUCACAUUCCACACCUCUUUCUGCCAAGACCACCACAAGCGUUCUCCCAAGCCCAUGUGCCCGCUUGAAAACUUGGUCCGCUUUGUGAAAAGGGACAUGUUUGUAGCCCUGGGUGGCAGUGGUACAAAUUAUUAUGAUGCAUGUCACAGGGAAGGAUUCUAAAAGGUAUGCAGUACAGCAGUAUAGAAUCCAUGCCAAUACAGAGCAUAGGGAAAGGUCCACUUCUAGUUUUGUCUGUUACUAAGGGUAGAAGAUUAUUGCUUUUUAAAGGCUAAAUAUUGUUUGUGGGAACCACAGAUGGUUGGGGUUGAACAGUAAGCACAUUGCUGCAAUGUGGUACGUGAAUUGCUUGGUACAAAAUGGCCAGUUCACAGAGGAAUAGAAGGUACUUUAUCAUAGCCAGACUUCGCUUAGAAUGCCAGAAUAAUAUAGUUCAAGACCUGAAGUUGCCAAUCCAAGUUUGCACUCUUCUGGCCUGCCCCAUGUUACUAUGUGAUGGAACCAGCACACCUCAACCAAAAUUUUUUUAAUCUUAGACAUUUUUACCUUGUCCUUGUUAAGAAUUUCUUGAAGUGAUUUAUCUAAAAUAAAGGUUGGCAAACUUUUUCUGUAAAGGGCCAGAUUGUAAAUAUUUCAGACUGUGUGGACCAAAAGGCCACAUACAGUCUCUGUCAUAACUACUCAACUCUGUUUCUGAAGCAGGAAAGCCACCACAGACAGUACAUAAAGGAAUAUGUGUAGCUGGGUUCCCAGGCCGGACAAAACAGAUGGUGACCAGAUUUGGCCCCUGGGCUGUAGUUUGCUGACCCCUCAUCUAAAAAAUAGGCUAUACUACAAUUGCACUUCCAGCACUUUGAGAACGAGUUGAAUACCAAGAAUUAUUCAAUGGUUCCUCCAGUAACUUCUGCUAGAAACACAGAAUUUGGUCUGUAUCUGACACUAGAACAAAACUUGAGGGUAAAUAAACAUUGAAUUAGAAUGAAUCAUAGAAAACUGAUUAGAAGAAUACUUGAUGUUUAUGAUGAUUGUGGUACAAGAUAGUUUUAAGUAUGUUCUAAAUAUUUGUCUGCUGUAGUCUAUUUGCUGUAUAUGCUGAAAUUUUUGUAUGCCAUUUAGUAUUUUUAUAGUUUAGGAAAAUAUUUUCUAAGACCAGUUUUAGAUGACUCUUAUUCCUGUAGUAAUAUUCAAUUUGCUGUACCUGCUUGGUGGUUAGAAGGAGGCUAGAAGAUGAAUUCAGGCACUUUCUUCCAAUAAAACUAAUUAUGGCUCAUUCCCUUUGACAAGCUGUAGAACUGGAUUCAUUUUUAAACCAUUUUCAUCAGUUUCAAAUGGUAAAUUCUGAUUGAUUUUUAAAUGCGUUUUUGGAAGAACUUUGCUAUUAGAUAGUUUACAGAUCUUUAUAAGGUGUUUUAUAUAUUAGAAGCAAUUAUAAUUACAUCUGUGAUUUCUGAACUAAUGGUGCUAAUUCAGAGAAAUGGAAAGUGAAAGUGAGAUUCUCUGUUGUCAUCGGCAUUCCAACUUUUUCUCUUUGUUUUUGUCCAGUGUUGCAUUUGAAUAUGUCUGUUUCUAUAAAUAAAUUUUUUAAGAAUACCUAUACUAUACAACUAAUGGUUUGUACCUAUAAGUCACUCGAGUUAUUUUCAAGUGAGAGCCAGUAUUUUAUUUUUCCCCCUUCAUUCAAAUGUCAUGCAGAGAACCAGUAUUUUAAAAUUUUAUUUUAACUGCUUUACUAACUGCUGAAAGUUGUGUUAUCUCUCAAGUAUUCAAAGACUAAAUGUGUUUUCUUUCCUUCCCACUCACAAUAUAUCUGAAUUAGAACUGCUAAACACAGCUUGAAGACUUAAAAAUAAAAGUGACUCGGAAGAUUUUUUAAAAAAUCAA